GGCCCCAGGACCCGACCCGGCCCCAGGAGAGUGUGCUCGUUCUGUUCACGGAGCUGGCCGCGUUAGCGACGUCCUCGAGUCCGCGGCGGGCACGAUGCAGCUCUUGGUGAGGGUACCCUCUCUUCCGGAGCGGGGCGAGCUGGACUGCAACAUCUGCUACCGUCCUUUCAACCUCGGGUGCCGCGCGCCCCGCCGCCUGCCCGGAACGGCGCGCGCCCGCUGCGGCCACACGAUCUGCACCGCCUGCCUCCGCGAGCUGGCGGCGCGCGGGGACGGCGGCGGGGCGGCCGCGCGCGUGGUGCGCCUGCGCCGCGUGGUCACGUGCCCCUUCUGCCGCGCGCCCUCGCAGCUCCCUCGCGGCGGCCUCACGGAGAUGGCUCUUGACUCGGACUUGUGGUCGCGAUUGGAGGAAAAAGCGCGGGCCAAGUGCGAACGAGAUGAGGCUGGGAACCCGGCCAAGGAAAGCAGCGACGCUGACGGAGAGGCGGAGGAAGAAGGGGAGAGCGAGAAGGGGGCGGGGCCUAGGAGUGCUGGGUGGCGCGCGCUCCGGCGGCUCUGGGACAGGGUCCUGGGGCCUGCGCGGCGCUGGCGGCGUCCGCUGCCUAGCAACGUGCUCUACUGUGCGGAGAUCAAGGACAUUGGCCACCUGACCCGUUGCACGUUGUAACCGAGGAACUCGGAAGCUACAGCCGAAGGAAGGUGGGAGCUGCAGCCUCGCGGGGGCUGAUGUCAAGACUACUCUCUCUCAGAUCCCAGGAUUGGCAUGUGAUGAGAGAGAUGAGCCGAAGGCAGGAGGGAACGCCCUGGGAGGUGUUGAUGCUGAGUUGGGGAGGCUCCUAGACGAACUCGCCCCCAUCUACUGACUGUGCCAGUCUUACAUUUUCAGGAUGGAGUGGCCAAGGGAUGAUAUAAACAAAGCCUACGUUACCGUGGGAAGAAGACAGACUGUUUUCUUAGCUGGGACGUUGGCUUUUGUCCAGGGUGGCUCUGGUGUGUGGGAGCAACAGGUCCCAUUUUAGCAAUUCUUUGUCAAUGGUUUGAAUUUUUUUUUUUUUUAAGAUGGAACGGGAGAGAAGAGGCUAAUUUUCGCGUCAUGUUAAUCUCACUUCUCUGGCAUGUAAGGGUGCUGGUAUGCCUGCUGUCUCCCCACUCCCAGUUCUGUGUUCCAGAAAUUGAGAUGGCUCCCUGCCUGUGACUAUGAUUAGGAGCCUUGCUUCAUUUCAGAAUCUCCCUUCAACCUGCUAGGGCAGGUAUCAGAAAUUCCAAAGGGCAUUUAUGUGAGGCACCUAAUUAGAGCCUAUCAAAGUAGGAAGGGAGAGCCAUUUGAAAGGCAUCAUAUUUCAAACUUUUGCUAUUAUCUGUGUUAUCUUUACAGUCACGGGAACACACUAGCGCUACUGAAAAGAUACUUAUACAAUUUUAAGUGUCUUUAAAAUUUGUGUCCCAUAAUGGGACAUCACCUGUUGUAUAUAUGCCAUGUAUUCUAUUUUAGAAUCCUGUAUCUUAUGACCAUAAAGUCAUAGUCAAGGACCAGCAGUGUUGGUGUACUGUCAACGGAAGUGCACAGUCUCACUCUAGGAUCCCACUCCAGACUUCCUGAAUCAGACUCUGGCAGGGUUUUUUGUUUUUUUGUUUUUGUUUUGAGCCAGAGUCUCACUGUGUCGCCCAGGCUGGAGUGCAGUGGCGUGAUCUCGGCUCACUGCAGCCUCCGCCUCCCAGGUUCAAGCGAUUCUCCUGCCUCAUCCUCCGGAGUAGCUGGGAUUACAGGCGCCUGCCACCACACCUGGCUAAUUUUUGUAUUUUUAGUAGAGAUGGGGUUUCGCCAUGUUUGUCAGGCUGGUCUCAAAACUCCUGACCUCAGGUGAUGGCGCCCACCUUGGCCUCCCAAAGUGCUGGGAUUAUAGGAGUGAGCCACCGCGCCGGGCCAGACUCUGGCAUUUUAACAAUCCCAGGUGAUGUGUGUGCAUGUGAAAAUUUAAGUACCAUUGGUCUAGAUCCUACACUCUUUAGGAUAUCACCAUCUGUAGGUAGAAUAUUUAAAGCAUAAUAGGUAUGACUGAUAGAUUAUUUUAUCCAAAGUUCUUUUUUUUUUUUUUUGAGAUGGAGUCUUGCUCUGUUGCCCAGACUGGAGUGCAGUGGCGUGAUCUCGGCUCACUGCAAGCUCUGCCUCCUGGGUUCACGCCAUUCUCCUGCCUCAGCCUCCCAAGUAGCUGGGGCUACAGGCACCCACCACCACGCCUGGCUAAUUUUUUUGUAUUUUUAGUAGAGAUGGGGUUUCACCGUGUUAGCCAGGAUGGUCUCGAUCUCCUGACCUCAUGAUCCGCCUGCCUCGGCCUCCCAAAGUGCUAGGAUUACAGGCGUGAGCCACCACGCCCGGCCCCAAAGUUCUAAAGUAACAUUCUAUUGCUAAAGAAAUCCUAACCUACUAUGUAACAUUUUUCUCUUAGUUAAAAAUGUGAACUUAUUAUUAACCUCAAUUUUUUAGAGGCCUCCAAUCUUUUUAAAAUAUAAAUAUUUUUGAUUGACAAAUCAUAAUUAUACACUUAUGGGGGUAUAAACCUCAAUUUUUGUAACCCUAUUUUGGCAUUUUCCUGUCCUUACAUCUCAGCUUAAAUGCUCCCUCUUUUGGGAGGCCUUUUUCUGCCUUCAACAUAGUAGAGCCUUUUCCCCCACCCCUCUGUAACAUAAUGCCCUGUUUUAUUUUUACUGCUUUUAUUUUCAUGCUUUGUGGGUGUCCCCACUGGAGUGUAAGCCCUAUGGGAGCAAGGGCUGACCUGUGACUGUUUUAUCUCCAGGGCCAACAGCAGUGUUACUGUAUAGUAUGUACUCAAUAAAUAUUUGUUGGCUUUA